CUCGUUGUUCCUGUCACUUGCCUCGAGGUGGGAGGCUGGGGUUGGAUACCCGCCCCCAAGCCCCAGGGCGGCCAGCCGCGGCCAGGUUUACAGUUGCCCAGGGGGUGGGGCGCCACACGUGUGUGUGUUGUGGGGCGAGGGCUCGCAUUUUCAUUAGGGGGACGUCACCACCCCCUCCAGUCACCGCUGCGAGUUUGGAGAAGUUUGUACGUGGGCUCUUGGGGGCGGUGGCCCAGGUUAGGGAGGGGAGGAGACAGUGCGACUCUGUGUGUGUGUGUGUGUGUGUGUGUGUGUGUGUGUGUGAGUUCGCGCACUUCCUAAGUACCUUCGAGGCAAGGGGAAUUGAAUGGUGGGCGGCGCUUCAGGGGUUGAGAGGGAAAAUGUGCAGAAGAGGACCUUUACACGAUGGAUAAAUCUACAUCUAGAAAAGUGCAACCCACCUCUAGAAGUUAAAGAUUUAUUCGUCGAUAUACAAGAUGGCAAAAUCCUAAUGGCUUUGUUAGAAGUCCUGUCUGGGCGGAAUCUGCUGCACGAAUACAAAUCCUCGUCGCAUCGUAUUUUUCGGUUGAACAACAUAGCGAAAGCACUUAAGUUUUUGGAAGAUAGCAAUGUAAAACUGGUUAGCAUUGAUGCAGCAGAAAUAGCAGAUGGCAACCCUUCUUUGGUUCUUGGGCUGAUAUGGAACAUAAUCCUCUUCUUCCAGAUUAAGGAGCUCACAGGCAACCUCAGCAGAAACUCUCCAUCUUCCAGCUUGUCCCCUGGCUCAGGGGGCACAGACUCAGACUCAUCCUUCCCACCCACACCCACUGCAGAGAGGAGCGUGGCAAUAUCGGUGAAAGACCAGAGGAAGGCUAUCAAGGCCCUGUUGGCGUGGGUGCAGAGGAAAACGAGAAAGUAUGGCGUGGCGGUGCAGGACUUUGCGGGCAGUUGGAGGAGUGGGCUGGCUUUCCUGGCGGUGAUCAAGGCCAUUGACCCCAGCCUGGUGGACAUGAAACAGGCCCUGGAAAAUUCCACACGAGAAAAUCUAGAGAAGGCUUUCAGCAUCGCACAGGAUGCCCUGCACAUCCCCAGGCUCCUGGAGCCAGAAGACAUCAUGGUUGACACACCAGACGAGCAGUCUAUCAUGACUUACGUGGCACAGUUUCUAGAACGUUUUCCGGAGUUGGAAGCCGAAGAUAUUUUCGAUUCAGAUAAAGAAGUUCCUAUCGAAUCCACUUUUGUUCGCAUCAAAGAAACUCCUUCUGAACAGGAGAGCAAAGUCUUCGUUCUGACUGAAAAUGGGGAGCGUACCUACACUGUUAACCAUGAAACCAGCCACCCACCACCCUCCAAAGUCUUUGUCUGUGACAAGCCCGAGAGCAUGAAGGAAUUCCGCCUGGAUGGUGUUUCCAGCCAUGCGCUGUCAGACAGCUCCACCGAGUUCAUGCACCAGAUUAUUGACCAGGUCCUGCAAGGGGGCCCAGGUAAGACCAGCGACAUCAGUGAGCCAUCUCCAGAAUCCUCCAUUUUAUCAUCCAGAAAGGAGAACGGGAGGUCCAACUCUUUGCCGAUCAAGAAAACAGUUCACUUUGAGGCUGACACCUACAAGGAUCCUUUCUGCAGUAAGAACCUGUCCCUUUGCUUUGAAGGGAGCCCAAGAGUGGCAAAGGAAUCAUUGAGGCAGGAUGGACAUGUCUUGGCAGUUGAGGUUGCUGAGGAAAAGGAACAGAAACAGGAAUCCUCGAAGAUUCCAGAAUCCUCCUCUGACAAGGUCGCUGGUGACAUUUUUUUGGUGGAGGGCACAAACAAUAAUUCUCAGUCUUCUUCCUGUAAUGGUGCUUUAGAGAGUACAGCCCGCCACGAUGAAGAAAGUCACUCUCUUUCACCCCCAGGAGAAAAUACUGUGAUGGCCGAUUCCUUCCAGAUCAAGGUUAACCUGAUGACUGUAGAAGCUUUAGAGGAGGGAGACUAUUUUGAAGCCAUCCCAUUAAAAGCCUCAAAAUUUAACAGCGACCUAAUAGAUUUUGCUUCUACCAGCCAGGCUUUCAACAAAGUUCCUUCACCUCAUGAGACAAAACCUGACGAGGAUGCUGAGGCUUUUGAGAAUCAUGCUGAAAAACUAGGUAAAAGGAGUAUUAAAUCUGCUCACAAAAAGAAGGAUUCGCCAGAGCCUCAAGUUAAGAUGGACAAACAUGAACCUCAUCAGGACUCCGGAGAAGAAGCUGAAGGCUGUCCUUCAGCCCCAGAAGAGACACCAGUGGAUAAAAAGCCAGAGGUGCAUGAAAAGGCCAAGAGAAAGUCCACCCGUCCUCAUUAUGAGGAAGAGGGAGAAGACGAUGACCUCCAGGGUGUGGGCGAGGAAUUAUCUUCCAGCCCCCCAAGCAGCUGUGUCAGCUUGGAGACCCUUGGGAGUCACAGCGAAGAAGGCCUGGAUUUCAAGCCCUCCCCACCCCUCUCAAAGGUUUCCGUCAUUCCCCACGACCUCUUCUAUUUCCCACACUAUGAGGUUCCCCUGGCUGCAGUUUUGGAGGCUUAUGUAGAAGACCCGGAGGAUCUAAAAAAUGAAGAAAUGGAUCUCGAAGAGCCAGAGGGCUAUAUGCCAGACCUGGACUCCAGGGAGGAGGAGGCCGAUGGCUCUCAGAGCAGCUCCAGUUCCUCGGUGCCAGGAGAGAGCCUCCCCAGUGCCAGCGACCAGGUGCUGUAUCUCAGCAGGGGUGGUGUGGGUACCACACCAGCCUCAGAACCCGCUCCACUGGCCCCCCAUGAGGACCACCAGCAAAGGGAGACCAAAGAGAAUGACCCCAUGGACAGCCAUCAGUCCCAGGAAUCCCCAAACCUGGAAAACAUAGCAAACCCCCUAGAAGAAAAUGUAACGAAAGAAUCAAUCAGUAGUAAAAAAAAGGAAAAAAGGAAACAUGUGGACCACGUAGAAAGUUCACUAUUUGUAGCACCAGGAAGUGUUCAAUCCUCAGAUGACCUAGAAGAAGACAGUAGCGACUACAGCAUUCCUUCCAGGACUAGUCACAGUGACUCCAGCAUUUACCUUCGACGACAUACUCAUAGGUCUUCGGAAUCGGAUCAUUUUAGCUAUGUUCAGUUGAGGAACGCAGCAGAUCUGGAUGACAGAAGAAACCGAAUAUUAACCAGGUACAGUACUCAGAAGCUUACUGAGCUGAUUUUACAGUUUUAUGGCAUCAGAGCAGACAUGAAGAGGGAAAGCAAACAUGCCAGGAUGUCUAUGAAAGCCAACAGCUCAGGAGAAGCCAUGUCACUGGGGAGCCACAGCCCGCAGAGUGACUCCCUGACACAGCUUGUCCAGCAGCCGGAUAUGAUGUAUUUUAUUCUCUUCCUGUGGCUCCUGGUGUACUGCUUGCUGCUCUUCCCACAACUGGAUGUUAGCAGGCUCUGAUACGUGUGUCUGGAUAAUAAAAAAGACAGGACCCUGACCAGGGGCGGGGUUACUUCAUUUUAUUUUGGGUUCUGGGUGGGGCACUUCUACAGACAGUUGAGGACCUCCGAGGAAACUUAGACCCCCUUUCUCGCUAUUGUGGUUUUUUUUUUUUUUUCAGGUUUCCUUUUUUUUCUGGACAACCUGAGCAUGCUUUUUUCUUUGGCUGUGUACUCAAAACUCAGGCAUGCAGCUGGAUCCGUAGGUGGGGUUUUGUCCUUGUGUGCCUUGCUGGGUUGGAUAGGGAGCAUUGUUAGUGAUCAUUAGCCCGCCUGGAUCUUAGCACACCCCACAUUGCAGGUUCACACGCUGGAUGAACUUGAGUUUCUUACCUCUCAGAUGAAGGGCUGCUUAAUGAGAAAGAGGGUGGGCACCCCAGGCCAAGCCCCAGCUGGGGAGAGAGCUGCCACGUUUUCCUCCAAGCGUGGGUGUUUGAGAGAAGGUGCUGGGGUCCAUGCACCUGUCGCAGUCCGGUAACUGGUUGCAUUCACUAGGGGAAAUCCGAGCAGCCAGCUCUGUGUAAGCACAUCCAGGAAUGGCAGAAUCCAGGGAGGAAGGUGAAAGCUGUGUUGAGAGCCACUGUGUGCUCUUUUUCACCCUGUUUUUUUUGUUGUUUUUUUGUUUUGUUUUUUGUUUGAGGGGAGAUAACACUUGAAAUUCAGUUUUCCAUUGAUUGGAUUGAGAUAGAACCAUGAUUUUCAAACCAGAUCGCCAGGGCCCAGCAGGGCCAUAUAAAAGCCAUGAGGAGUGGCUGGGCUGGAAUCAGCUCCCAGCAGUGCUGGAGCUGGGUGGUGGGGUAGCUUCCUGCCCACUAAAGCUUUGGUGCACACCUCCCUCAGAAUGCAUGUCUUGGAACGGGCAUUCUUUGUGGUCACUUGUAAUGGGUUUCUUGAAGAGGCUUUCUGGACAGCACUCCGGGAGCAGGCCAGCACAGGAGGUUUGUGAAAGAAGAGAGGCAUCUCUAGCACCCCUGCCCCCAGUCUUCCUCAGCCCCAGGCUCCCUCUGCUCUCUCCUCCCUGCCAAGACUCAGGUCCGUGGUGAGUCUCUGCAUUGGUUCCUCCUCCCCUUGCUCUCCCCUUCAGAAAGCAUGUACCAGGCAACCCUUAUAAAAUCACAAAUGAGUCAGGAGGGGACUCAGUGAGCAUCUUGUCUAGCUGGACCCAGAGAGACAGAGCAGCUUGACCAAGAUCAUAUAGCCGACCAGGGGCAGACUUGCAGUGAGCACACAGGCACCUGAUGCCCUGUCCAGAGCUGUCACCCCUUGUAGGAAACUUCCACUGGGCACACCAAUGUCCUGAGAAAAAGAUAAAAUGACUAGAUUAAAAUGUCCACAUUCAAGCAAAACCAAAAAGUUUAGACCAACUAUCGACAUUUGUUUUGUUCUUGUAUUUUUCCCAUGAGGAAUUCUUACUCACCUUCAAGCUCAUCCCCAAUUCCUUCUGAAAUACCCUUGACAGCUGCAACAGCUUGUCAUUUGACAUACCAGCGUCGCUCUUACUCCAGGAAUCACGUUUCUUUCUUUGCUAGCCAAGGACUUGCUCAUUUCAAGCAGUGGGUUUCAAGUUUACAGAAUUCCAGCAUGGCCAGAAGAAUUUACAUAGCACAUCUGAGUCGAUGACAGCCAAAAUCUGGCCUCUAAACCAGUCUGAUUAUAGUCUGUCUCCCCUCCUGAAAGAAUUUCAGCCUUCCAACCAGAAAGCUGCUGGGAGCUUGGAGUGAUUCCAUCUGGAAGGCCAAGAGCCCCAUGGAAAAUGAGCUAAUUAAUGAGCUCCCUGGCAUCAAUGAAAGCUCAAAGGUACAGAUAAUAAAGAUUAUGUGAUAGUUUAUAACUCUGGGCACCAUGCAGUCCUUGCCUAAAUUAGAUGCUCGAAGAGCCUGGGAAGAGCCAACCCAAAUGUGAAUCAUUUCAUUUUAUGGGUCUAGACCUUGUUCAGAAAAACCUCUGCAAGAUACUUCUCUCACCUAUUACAACUUGUAAUAUUGUUUAAAACAUCUACUGGCAAGAUGCCUGAAAGUCAUUUGGUUCAGGUUGGCAGUCAACUGAUAUUUUGCAAAGGAAAAAAAAAUCUCAUUUGAGUAUAGGCUUCUAUGGAAGAAGCUGGAUAUAGAAAAUGGAUGUGGAAGUCUGCAGGACAAACCACCCCAUUGCUUGUAAAUUUUUUUUAAAUUAAAAGAAAUACAAUAAGGCUUUUAACAAGAACUAGCAGUCCCCUAAGUCUCGCUGCUUAGAAGUAACCACUUUCAACUCUCUUAUGUUUGCAUUUCUACAUAACGUGCUUACACUUUAUUUUUUAAUUUAGAAACAUCUACUGGCUUGCUGUCACAGUAGAGGAGGAUUUCACUCUUACCAUACCGUGCUUUGGUUUUCCAGUAUAGCUAGAUCACAUCAUUUAGUACAUUUCUAUUAGGUGUUGACAUUACCUGGAGCACUUAAGGAUUGUUGACUCCCAAGCCCAGCAGUGUGUUAUGGUUACAUGUCCUUUCUCCUCCAAAUGUCCCCAUUAAUUUGCUAUUCUCUCUCUUUACUUUUUUUUUUUUUUUGGUGUGGCACAUUCUUUAAUAACUUCCUGAGGAAGAGAACAUGGGAAGUAAAUAUGGUUGUAAAUAUUUUGAGAUUUUUGCAUGACUUAAGAUGUCUGUAUUCUGCCCUUAACAGAAAUGUGGCUGAGCAUAGAAUGACAGGUGGAAAAUAAUACCCUCCCCUAGCCCCUCCCAAGCGUGCUGGUUGAGAUUUCUGAUGCCAUUCUGAUUCCCGUACCUUUAUAUGUGACUUAGGUUUUUUUAUCCACCCUUCCUGGAAACAUUUAAGAUCUCUUUAUUCUUGGUGUUCUGAACUGUCAUGAUGGUGUUGUAUCCCGGGUGUUAAACCUUGUGCUGGGCCUUCAUGGGAAAUUUCUUAAAUUUUCUUGUGAUUAUUUACAUUCUUUCUUUCUGGACCACCUAUUAUUUCAAUGUUGGACCCUCCCCUACACCCAGGCUGAUGCUCUAAUAUUUUUUAUCUUUUCUAUUUUUCGUCUAUGUUUCUGAUCUGCUUUCAGGAAGAAUUAUUCAUUUUUAUCUUCCCAAUCUGAAUGUUUUAUUGAAUUUUUAUUUUCCAAGUUAAUAAAACCUUUGGUUAUUAUCCUGUCUUUGUUUUACAGUGUCCUGCUCUUGAUGCGUGGAUGCAGAUUUUGUCUCUCUGUGGACGUUAAUGAUUGUGGUCUGAGGGGAAGUCUUUUCUGCUCCCUGUGUUGCCCUCAUUUUCUCUGAGUUCUCUUUAUUUUGGUGGUCUCAGUCUCUAUCUUUCACGUUGUGAAUUUUUCUCAAAUAUAUGGUGAUCCUAUGGAUCUGUUCAUGUUUUAAGAGUGAGGCAUCCAAAAGCUGAUUGGAAGUUGUGUGUGCCAACUGGUGAGCUUUUCCACUAGGGUCACCAGGUGGGCACCUGGACUCAUCAUUGGAGAACACUGCCUGUCAGUAUUUGCACGUGUUUUCUCUGGGGCUCAUUCUGUUUCUUGAGAGAUAUUCCCACUACUCUCCUUCCUGGGAAACGGGCAUACACAGGGCUUUUAGCCUAUGCUGAGUACUCAUGUGGUUUCAAAAAUGGUGUCCCAUCUGGGCAGAAGUCCCCAUGAGCACUUGGCUUGACUGGCAAAGGACACCUUUUGCCCCUUCCUCCAGACAUACCCAGCUCUGAGCUUGGACAAUGCUCGAGGAACAAUGAAAAGGCUAGAUUUUAACUCCUAAUUGCCCUCUUUAGCCAAGUGCCUCUGUGCAAUGCACAACUGUAGGACCAUAUCCAGAGACCCUGGUCUAUACUCAGUGUGCCCGAGUCCUGACCGCUGAGCAGGCAGCCUCAUCACCCGUGAGUAUUUAGACUUUCAUUAAGUUGCUUCAACCUUUGCUGUGCCUGGUGUCCCUGAGUUGGAGCUGCUCUGAUUUCUCCAUGGAGUAGGAGCACAGUGGUCAUCUGGCUGCAUGGGAAGGACAGGGGACCUCAGAGCCAAUAAAUGCCCUGGUCUUCAGCCCCAUGUCUCACCCCAUCCCUCCUAUUCCAAUCCCCAAGCCUCUCCUGGAGGCCACAGGGCAUCUCUGCUGACCACUCUGUGGCCUCCCCUCUGCAGGCAUGUGGUUUUAGGAUCCCCCUCCCUGCUCACUUUUCCAUCAGUUCCAUUCCUGCAUAAAUAGGUUGCUAGCUCUUGCUUACUGUUCUCUUCUGUAUUCUGUGUUCAUGGUUGUAUUAAUAUAACUUUCAUUCCUCUGCUCCUAUUUUCAUGGGGUUUCAUGAGGGAAGAAACAGGCUCAUGUGUUCAGUAUACCAUCUUGAUCCAUAAACCCCAUUUGAGUUAUCUCACAGGUUGCUUAGGGGGCUUGCUGCUCUGACUGGUUUGUGAACGUGCCCUGAGUCCAGCUGGGACUGCAGCAACAUCCAUCCUGUUGAGCUGUGGUCUGCUAAGUGAUUUUGUGUAAUGCUGUGCCAAGUGCAGGAGAGGGAUACAUAGCAUGGCUAAGCUCUGCUUGAAUGCCAUGAUUAGUUAUUACCUUCCUUCCUUCCCCCUGGUUUUGCUGCCUAUUGUCAGUAAAUGAUCUUAGAUCUCCUGCCUCCCCAAAGAUAUAGUCUAUGUGGUGGUCUGGGUUCUAGGUUUUCUUUACCACCCUUGCUUCACUUAAGAAACAGAAAACUGGCUAGGCACAGUAGUGGCUCACACCUAUAAUCCCAGCCCUUUGGGAGGCCAAGGCAGGAGGAUCGCUUGAGGCCAGGAAUUCAAGACCAGCCUGCACAACAUAGCAAGACUCCAUCUCUACAAAAAGUUAAAUUUAAAUUAGUGGUGGCAUACACUUAUAGUCCCAGCUACUCAGGAGGAUGAGGCAGGAGAAUUGUUUGAGCCCAUGACUUUGAGGUUACUGUGAGCUAUGAUCCUGCUAUUUUACUCCACCUGAGUGACAGAGCGAGACGCUGUCUCAAAAAUAAAGAAACAAGUAGUCCACACAGGUGUUUGCCAGCAAACAAACAGCGCGGAUUCUCUGUUGAACGUGGCCAACAUUGCCUCGUCGAAGUUUGUAUCUUGCCAUAGUUGAUGAUCAGGUGGUCGGGGCUUCCUGGUCAGACCUGACCUUUGUGGGGAGAUGUUCUCCCACCAAGGCUCAGAAGCAGGACACUCUUGCUGCCCCUCGGGCAGCCACCCAGAACAUGGGCGUCUCCAUUUCUGAGGUUCAGCAUAGUUCCCCCCACCCUCUUCCCAUGCAGUGCAUGCCUGCUCUUUAUCAGGAUGGAACAGAGGGAAGGCAGAGGCACUGGGGGCAGCCUGUGUUGUUGAUCUCUGUAAGUCACAGACUGUUCGAAAACCUCAGGAAUUAUGUAAGCGUUCAGUGCCUCAUUUAAGAGAUGAAAAACUGAAGAUUAGAAAGAGGAAACGACUAGUCGCCCUGCUAGUUGAUGACCUCCAGAUAGCCAUCUUCAUUCCCAGUUAAGUUUACUACAAAACCACAGCCUCAGCUGCUGAAGCUAACCUCCCUACCCACCAUCGCUAGGGACUCAGAACACCAUGGAGCUCAUCUCUCCAACAAAAGUCAGAAUUAGCAAGUACAGAUGUGUCUUACGAAAAUGUCAGAAUCCAUCAUGGCUGCUUUGGUGAGGAGCUGUUCUCCUUCCGUGGUCAUGCCAUUGGAAGGCAGUUGUAUGACAAGAAUGCUUUCACAUGAGCUCCGAUUUUCUUAACUCUCCAGAAGGACUUCAGAAGCCUCUGGAGUUUUGAGACACGGCCUCUCUCUCCCUUCUGCUUGGAGACACCUUCCUGGGGGUCUCCACUGCAUUCCCCGCCGGUAUUCCUCUGUGGAGCCUUGCGCCCUCAGGUCCCAGAAAUGGGCUGUGUGGGAGCUUCCAGUCAGCCUGGUAUCUCGGGACCUUCUCAGCCAGGAAAUGAGACUGCACAAAGCCCUGUGAGGCCCAGCUGUGUUAUUUCUCCUUCCCCGACAUUGCAUAAUCACUGCUGACACAGCAUUUGGGGAAGAUUUAACGUCUUGGGCCAGCAGCUGCCAUCUGGAACCAUCACCACAUAGCAGGUUGUUCUGUCCCAUCCAACUGAUGAGGGGGCUGCCCUAAUGACAAGGUCCAGGACCUGGGUUGGGUGGUGGAAGGCUGGGAGCUGGAGUGGGCAUUAUUGUGCUUCUGUGCUGAAAAUUGCUAUGGCUCUUUUCCCCUAACAGCCAGCGUGGGAGAACCAAACAUGAGACACAAGCAUCCCCUUGAGCUCCACAGAUCUUGCGCCUUGCUCUCAUCAGGCAUUUCCUUGGAAAACAGCAGUCAGCAGCUCAUGGAAGUGAGCCCGGUGCACAGACUUUGCAUGGACUUUGCACAGGUUCCAUUUCCAUCGUGUGCAGACACCUGUAUCUUUGGGCUCCACGUGAGCACCUGCCCUCUUCACUCUGAUUUUUUUUUUAAGAGACAGCAUCUUACUCUGUCACCGAGGCUGGAGUACAGUGGUGUGAUCACAGCUCACUGCAGCCUGAAACUCCUGGGCUCAGGCAAUCCUCCUGCCUCAGCCUCCCAAGUAGCUGGUAGUACAGGUGCAUGCCACCACGCCCACCUAAUUUUUUUAUCUUUUAUAGAUACAGGUCUCACUGUUGCUCAGGCUGGUCUCGAACUCCUGGCCUCAAGUGAUCCUCCUGCCUUGGCCUACCAAAAUGCUGGGAUUAUAGGCAUGAACCACUGUGCCUGGCCUUCACUCUGAUUUUUCUUAAGAGUCCUACAGGACCUUCAGGUCUUGUCACUUCUCUACCAUUGUGUGUGAGACAGGGCAUGGGGUGAGCUUGGUCAGGUGUGGGUCAAAAGCCUGGAGACUCAGAGCUGCUGGUUCCCCAAGAGCCCACAAAAGUUAUCAGAGUUUCUGAGCUGAGUGUUCUGCAGUUGCCAGACCCCACAAUGCUGGGAAUACUGGCUUCUUUGUGUUUAGAACUUGUUCUGAGAACCUUGAUGAGAACACAUCAAGCAAGCAGUUCCUCCCAGCCAGGGCUGGAGCAACAUGCCAAAAAACAUUCUUGUCUAUGGGAAAAAGACAACCAGUAUUUUGUACUGUUUGACCAAGUUGUUUUUAAAUAUACACAUGCCUCAACAAUCCACGGCCUCAAUCGCACUGCUAAUUUGUUUAAAUCCCUGACACUCAGAUGUCAAGAAUAGCUUCAUCUAGCAGUGUUCUCUUUAAAGGAACCCUUUUUUUUGUUUUCAUUUUAAUCACUGCCUUCUUCUCUGGGAGGUAUUGUGGGCUAGAGAAAGAAGUCAGGUUUGGGAGUCAGCCAGAUUUAGAUUGGAGUCCCAGCUCUGUCACCAGAUCUCUGGGUGAUCUUGGCAAACUAACUUCUGAGCUUCUGUGCAUUAUAGGCAUUCAGCACAUAUUUGUUGGAUGAAAAAUACUUUUCUUGAAAGUUUAUGAAGUUGUAGGAUGCCCAGCAGCCCCCUUUUCUCUAUUUCCUUCCUCUUGAAGCAAGCGUUGACUAUACCUCUUUCCCUAACCCUUAGUGUACCAUAGCUUCUUCCAACCUCUCUCCAAUCCAUUACUUUUUUCUGAGCUACCCUGUCUCAAAUCUAACUCAGGCCUUUUUGCAAGAGGAAGUUUAAGCCAUUGUUUACUCAUUAACUCACUUGACCCUUAGAACAAUCGUGGGAGGUGUUUAUUUCGGAAAGGAAGCUAAAGCACAGGACAGAAAAAUAAGGUCAUAGCGUGAACUAGUAAGUAGCAGAACUGGGAACAUAGGACUGUUAUUUUCAAACACUCUAAACUUCACUGCAGUUGCAAAUUUGCAACCAAAAUGGCCGCCUUGAAAGGGUCUUUUGCAGUAAAAUCUCAGUGUCCAACAUCAAAGACAGUUCUUCAGGGCCUCCAAUUAACUAUACAUCCUGCCCCCAGCUGCUCAUCUCUGCACCUCUAACACGUACUUCACAGAGUAGGAAAUUGGGCUUUCUCCUUCAAAAAGAAAAGUAGAGAAGGCCUGAGGGCAGUGUAAUUAAAAUGGAGAAGUAGAGACCACGAAUUACUUGGAUGAAUUCAUAACUGGUUGGUCUCUGAGGCAGGGAUUAUUAUUUUUCCUGUAUUUUAAGCUUAAAAGUAGUGAUUUUUGCAUUGUUACAAAAAACAAAAUAGCAAAAUAUCAUUUGAUACUUGUAUUCUGUUUGCAAUAGCUACCACUUCCUUUAGCCCCAGCAAAAAUCAAUAGGUGUGUAUUCUCUACAAGCCCAUGCUGUGCCAGAAUGCCAGUAUUGCUAAAUGUCAUGCAAGGAUUUAGACACUUUUUUAAAGGAAACUCUGGGAGUGCCUGUUGUCUGGAGAGUUGACAUUGUCCAAAGCAGGCCAACACUGGUAUGGGUAUGGAGAACCCACGUCCUAGCUGUGGCUCACCUGCAGAUGCCUUGAAUUUACCUCUCUGGGUUGGAAGUGGGAAGACUUCUUUUAAAAGUCCUUUCUAAGUUUAAAAAUCCAAAGGUUACGAAGGUAGUUUUUAUUUAUCUCAAUAAGUGGCCUAUUUGCUUAAAGCAAGUGUACCUCUGUAUAUCAGCCCAAAGCUUAGGGCAGUGCUUCUUGGCUUUAGUAUCUGAGAAAGGUGCCUUUGGGAAGAGUUUGGUCAGACAGAAGGUAGUCUGAAUCUUAAAGGUUUCAGAUGAAUGUUUGAAGUAGAACCUGGGAAAUCUGCUUCCUAGGGCUGUUAGAAGGAAAUUGGUCUCCUUAAAUUACGUCAGCAUCUGAGGCAGUUUCCUAAGGGAAUUUCUUUUAAAUUCAAAAGUUCAACUGCAGGAAUAAAUAGCUGUACAGGACUAGAUCUUCCCAUCCCUCAUCUUUUCCCCUUCCCCGAGUAACGACUCAAAAAGGCUUCUGAAAUUCUACUCAGAAUCGGAGCCGUUUGCAUUCCAACAAGGAUCCCUUAAGCCAAAUGCUGGUGUGUUUGUGUAGAAUGUCCCUGGGGUAGGGGCGGUAGCUGUGGGGAGGGAAUGUGGUGCAGGGGACACCUGCCCUCUGCCCUUGAAAUUGCACCAUAAGAUGCUGCCUAUGUCACUCACAGUGGUGCUGAUACUAUCCGCCAAAGACAAAUUGUGAACACGGAAAAAUGGUCGUUCCCUACUGUACAUCCUCAGGACAGACUUAACUAAACUUGGAGACAGGAGAUUGUUCAGACCAUAUUGUAGUGGGUGGUGAUCAUUGUUUUAUUUUGGGGGAGUCUGGUCUAUUGAGCAGAUUGAAUGUUUCCUUAUUGUGCAGGGCUUAAUUGACUAUGUCUGAAAGUUUUUACUGAGAGCUCUAAGAAAACUAUUGAGGAAAAUGAAAUGUUAUUUUGUAGUACAAGGAUUAUUUUUGUCUAUUUAGGAUAUACAUAGCUGUAGCUUUGUAAAAAAAAAGAUCUUUAUAAACAAUAUAUGAAUGUGCCGUCUUAUUUAUUGAUUACUGUAAAUUAAGAUAUAAAUGGCUAUUUGAAUAAUUUAUACCUGUGGGAAUUAACUGGAGUAUUUGUUAUUUGACUGUUUUCUAUUAAGGAAUAUUAGGCUUGGUGCUAUGAUGAAUGAUCUUGUAAAAUCAUGUGUAUUCUUAAGAAAAUUUUUGAAUAUAAAUUUCUUGAACUGA